CCAGUGUUCCCAGUUCCCACCAGUCCAACUGCGAGGAGUGCGACGUGAGUCUGAGUCUGAUCCCUCCGAAAACCGUACUUCCGGCGCUGUCUCGGAGGCCUCCCGUCCCCUCCCUUGUCCGUCUUCUAACUCUUCCCCACGCCAGGUCCGUCAAGCCUAAGUCCUUGAGUUCCGGGUCCGGGCAGCAGAGAAAGGAAGUCCUCUCCCUGGAGGCCUAUCUCCCUCAGAACUGCGCGAGAAGCGAGACCUUAGAAGGCAGGGCUUCCCGCGAAGGACCGGAAAGGAGCGCCUACUAAGGACGCCGUCGAGGUCCGGGGCGCCUCAACUCUAUAGCUCUAACUGGCUAGAAGUGCCCAACGUGGAAUGUUUCUUUUUUAAAGGCGGCUCUUGAAGCGACCCGGAAGCGGAAGUGGAAGAAAGUUCUAGUGGCUUGAGAUUAAGCCUGAUCAAGAUGACAACCUCCCAAAAGCACCGAGACUUCGUGGCAGAGCCCAUGGGGGAGAAGCCAGUGGGGAGCCUGGCUGGGAUUGGUGAAGUCCUGGGCAAGAAGCUGGAGGAAAGGGGUUUUGACAAGGCCUAUGUUGUCCUUGGCCAGUUUCUGGUGCUAAAGAAAGAUGAAGACCUCUUCCGGGAAUGGCUGAAAGACACUUGUGGCGCCAACGCCAAGCAGUCCCGGGACUGCUUCGGAUGCCUUCGAGAGUGGUGCGACGCCUUCUUGUGAUGCUCUCUGGGAAGCUCUCAAUCCCCAGCCCUCAUCCAGAGUUUGCAGCCGAGUAGGGACUCCUCCCCUGUCCUCUACGAAGGAAAAGAUUGCUAUUGUCGUACUCACCUCCGACGUACUCCGGGGUCUUUUGGGAGUUUUCUCCCCUAACCAUUUCAACUUUUUUUUGGAUUCUCGCUCUUGCAUGCCUCCCCCGUCCUUUUUCCCUUGCCAGUUCCCUGGUGACAGUUACCAGCUUUCCUGAAUGGAUUCCCGGCCCCAUCCCUCACCCCCACCCUCACUUUCAAUCCGUUUGAUACCAUUUGGCUCCUUUUUUGGCAGAACAGUCACUGUCCUUGUAAAGUUUUUUAGAUCAAUAAAGUCAGUGGCUUUCA